CGGCAAUGAGAGUGGCACUAGCUGCCUUUAUCGGGUUUUGUUCUCUGGAAAGGGAUGGGGAGAGAUCAUUCCCUCCGCCCCAGCCUGUUGCCUGUGAAUUCUCACCUUUCUCUUUAGGCUGGAGAGGGUGGGAGAGAGAUUUGACAUCUUCCAGGGGGUAAUUUAAAAAUAUGAAUCUUGAUUUGGAAGCAGUUGCACACAAAGCAUCAUUCAGGAAAUACAUCACUCGCUUUUCAAAGCUGUAUGCCACGUUUUAAACAAGGACUUUUGACUCAUGUAGUGUUUCUUUUAGUAUUUCAGUUUACGUUAAGUUUAUGAAUCCAGACGUUCGUUUGUACCAGGAGCUAAAGUACACUUAUGCAUGGGCUUUGCUGUGUAUAUUAUGCUUUUUAAAAUCACAGAAAUCAGAAACAAAGUUGAGUGAAAAGCGGUGGCGGUGCAGGAGGAGGAACACUUGUGAGCUCCAGCUUAUUGGAACUGCCUUUAAGAAUUUCACAUUCUUGCGGCAAUAGUACUUACUUGUAAAUUGGCCUUCUUCCCAGGACAGGUUUUGAUAUUUCUUUUGCAUGUACUUCGAUGCAGCACUAAUGAAGUUGGAUCUCAGUAGAUCAAUUUUAUUUACUUUGCUAGAUUUGAUUCCCACCCCCACACCUCUUUAGAAAAUGGACUUUGGCAGGUAAAGAAGGAAGCGGGAAUCUGGUAUCCUUUUUGGCUUGUCAAAGCUUUGUUGAGCCAUGAAUAACAAAGUUUUGGCUUUUUAGCUUGUCCGAGUCCCACAUGUGAGUUUUCCCAUGGGGUAAAAGUAGGCCAAAUGAGAACCAAAGUAGAAUAACAUCACUUUUAAUUCGGCCCACUUGUGUGUUACAUUCUCCAUAUAUCUUGUUUCUCUCAUCAACUUUGAAAUUUUUUCAUUAUUUAUUCAUUUAGCCACUGAUAAAGUACCUACUGCAUGCCAGCCAUUGAUGGCGGGGGUUGCUUCUUGCCCAGUUUUCUCAUUUGGAAACUGAUCCAUGCCUUUAUCCCACUAGUUACCCUGAAGUAAUUUGAACUUAGGGAGCAUUUCUGCCUGGAGACCUGUAAGAAUAGGUGUUACGUAGGCACUUAGUCUUCAGAUUGGUUUGGGAUUUCGUACAUUGUAGGCACGUAGCACGCAGGCCACUUAAAAAUAAAUGUAUGUGUCUUUGGGCUGUUGUAUUACGAGCUUUGCAUAUGGGCUUGUCUGGCCGAAGGACCCAGUGUCCGAGGUGGAGGUAGUAGUCAGGGACAUGUAUUAUUCAUUUCAGAACACUUGGCACCUUUUCUUGCUUACAUUGGGCACUAAAAUAUUUACUGAAUUGACUUGAACAGAAAAAUGAAGGAUUUUUUAUACCAGAUUAAGAAAUUUGGACUUUAUCCAGUCAGUGAUACUGAGCUGCUAAUUUUAAGCAGGAGAAUGUCAUGAUAACGGGUAAGCAUUCCAGAAAGAUAUCUGCAGCGUCUGGAGGAUGGUGGGCUUCCAGAUGGGCGAUAUGGAGACUAAGUUGGAGGCUGUUCUAAUGGAGGGGUUAAGUGCUCAGGGAUUCUCUAUUCAGAUUACCUGGGGUGGAAUCAGGCUCUGUCAUACACUGAAACCUCUUUGUUCCUUAGGUUUGUCAUCUCAGAGUUUGGGGGAUAGAACUUGAAAAAACAUGUCUAUUACUUAGAAUAGUGAUUGCCAGAUAGUAAGGACUUAGUAAAUGCUAGUGUGCUGGCAGUGGAAGGAGAAAUGACGUGGUGUUUAAGAGGUAUGACUAGGAGGCUGGACUAGGUAAGUGACUGGGUAGGCUUAAGGAGGGAAGGAUGAAUCCUGGGUUGUUUGACUUCAGGCAUUGAUUGACAUGUACUGGGUAAGCUGGCUGUGAAAUUAAAACGGGUCAAAUUCUAAUUCUAUUACUUACCCUUAGAAUAACUAUCCUGACAGAACUUUGAUUUCCUAACAUUUGGGAAAUGAUUGUCGUACCUGUUGAGUAGGGUUUGAGGAAUUAUGCAUGUAAUGCCUUUGGCAGGGUACCUAGCACAUUCCAAGUGCUCAGUAAAUAUUAGUUGUUCCUUUAGAUGAUGACAUUAAUGAGCUAGUGGAAUGUUGGAGGAUAUGAGAAGGAGCAGUUAAAAACAAUUGAUGGUAGAGGUGUAGAAGGGAAGAUAAGUUCAGUUUUGGACUAAUCUAAGGAGGUGCUAAAUGGAUGGUUGAGAGAUCCAUGAUGCAGUUGUUGGAUAGUUGUGUCUCACAGGAGCUAGGAAAGAAUAGAAAAGAAAAAGAGUUCACAGAAAGGCUUUAUGAGUAUGGUAAGCUUUAUGAGAGAUUUAGAGGAAGGGGAGGGUGAAGGGGUUCACAGUGGAGCGAUAUCAGAAGUGUUGACAUUGAAUAUUAGGCAUUUCUAUCCUUAAAAUAUAUUUUGGCCACCAUCAAAGAAAGGAGGACUCCAGGCUCUUGUAAUCUGGUUGGCUCUUUGGCCUUCUUCCCCUCUUCUUUCUUUCCUUUACAAUUGCCACCCGAUAUCUUUAAAUUGUAUUAUGAGGAACUAUUUAACUUUCCUUCCUGCUUACAGGGCUAGAGUUCACAGGCCCACCUUCCUCUAUCCAAAUGCAUCUAGGUUUUUAAAAAAGAAUCACAGGUCUCAUUUCAUAGGUUCUCCUCUAUUUAGGAAGCAGUGUUGUUUGAAAAAGUAAUACAUAUGUAUCUUGCAUGUAGAAUUAGAAGACUGGGGCAGGCCUACCUAAAUUGACCCUGUAGGAGGGCCUGAGAGUCUUACAAAAGACAUCCCUUUUAGCUUUCCUGGCACCUGUUUCUUUUCCUCAGAAAAUACAAAGCAGUAGGAAAAUCUGUGGUUAAUAAGUUAUUUUGUUUGGUUGGAUUCAGAAAAGGUGGCUAUUUUGUGUAUUAGCCUUCUAAGAAGUUAUUAAGAGGAAUUUUUUGGCCAGGUGCAGUGACUCACGCUUAUAAUUCUAGCACUUUGGGAGGCUGAGGCGGGCGAUCACGAGGUCAGGAGUUCAAGACCAGCCUGGCCAACACAGUGAAACCCUGUCUCUACUAAAAAUACGAAAAUUAGCUGGGCGUGGUGGCAGGUGCCUGUAAUCCCAGCUACUCAGGAGGCUGAGGCAGGAGAAAUCGCUUGAACCCGGGAGCUAGAGGUUUCAGUGAGCUGAGAUUGCGCCACUGCGCUCCAGCCUGGGUGAUAGAGCUAGACUCCAUCUCAAAAAAGGAAUUUUUUAACAAGCAAGUGCUCAUGACAUUACAAUAAUAAAUUGUCCUCUAGUUAGUAUGCUUUUAAAGAAGCAGGUGUUGUAGGUUCUAUCCUUUAGAAUGUGUGCUUCCUAGAGCUGGGAUCCUAUCUAUUUUGCUAACUGCAGAAUCCCUAAGUACUUAAACAAAUAUUAAUGUAUUGUAAACCAAAAAUAAAAUUCUAAGCUUCCCCCUCUCCCCAGCCAUCUGAAUGGACUUCCUCCUCAUCCAGGGGUCUUUUAAAAUUUAACCUGAGAGACAGUUUCAGGCCAUGAGUGGGAAGUGGAGGUCGGACAUGACUUGUUAUACCUCUCUGACAUUAACAUUAACAUAGACUUUAAGUCCGAUAAGAAACGUUUUACUACCACCUAUCGAAGCCUACUACCUGAAGGCUUCCUCUGAAAGUAAGAACUUGGGUCUCCACAAUCCUUUGUCUUAACCCAGACAUUCCUUUCUGUUGAUCCCAGGGCUUUAGACAAACUCAACCGACUGUCAACCAGAAAAUGUUUAAAUUUACCUAUGGCUUGGAAUGGCACUCCCUGCUACCCCCCCCAACCCCCCACCCCACCCCCGACCCCCUGCAAUUGUCCCACCUUUCUGGACCAAACCAAUGUAUUUCUUAAAAUUUUUUGAUUGAUGUCUCAUGCCUCCCUAAAAUGUAUAAAACCAAGCUGCACCCCUACCAUCUUGGGCACAUGUUCUUAGGACCUCCUGAAGGCUGUGUCAUGGGCCAUGGUCACUCAGAUUUGGCUCACGAUAAAUCUCUUCAAAUAUGUUGCAGAGUUUGACUCUUUUUGUUGACAGCAUGCAUUAAUGAACAAAUUGGAUCCAAAUUGGCUUUGAUCUGGCUUGGCUCACAGACUUCUCCAAAUCUUUGAAACAGUCAUUGGUCAGAGGGAAAGCAAAAGAGAAUUGAUCCAGUGAGGAAGCUUGAACUGUUCCCUGUUCUUAUAGGAAUAUAGAAGAACUGCAACAUUGAUGGCUUAUGAUUAAGCUUCUGUGAUGUUGUGAAAUAUAUAUAUGGUCUUUAUCCCUGUUUCCUGGCAUACAACUCUCAAAUUCCUUGGAAUCUGCAAAGCGCUAAGUGUCUUUGUAUGCUGAUGAGUUGACUGAACAGCUGGCAGCCCCUAGGUAGCUUCAGGAUGGGCCCUGGGCACUGGAAAGGCUGGAUUAGAGGGUUAGGACUGUCAGCCCCACCACCACCCUCCAGGGAGGGCAGAGGAGCUGAAGGGUAAGCUGAUCACCAAUGGCCAAUGAUUUAACCAACCAUACCUAUGUUAUGAAGUCUUCAUAAAAGGCCCAAGAGGACAGGGUUCAGAGAGCUUCUGGACAGCUGAUCACAUGGAGGUUCCUGGAGGGUAACACGCCCCAGAGAGGGCAUGGACGCUCCGCACCCCUUCCCCGUACCUCGCCCUGUGCAUCUCUUCAUCUAUAUCCUUUGUAAUAUCUUUUAUAAUAAACUGGUAAACCUAAGUAAGUGUAUCCCUGAGUUCUGUGAGCUGCUCUAGCAAGUUAAUUGAACCCAAAGAGGGGUUAUGGGAACCCCAAAUUGAGGCCAGUCAGUUAGAAUUUUCUGAGGCCUGCACUUGCGACUGGUGUCUGGUGGAGAGGGGAGCGGUCUUGGAGACUGAGCCCUCAGCUUUGGGAUCUGGGGUUAUCUCCAGGUCAGAAUUGAAUUGAACUAGAGGACACUCAGCUGGUGUCCACUGCUUUGUGUACUGGGGUGUCGGGGGGAGCCCACAUUUGGACAUAGAAGUAUUCUGUGUUGAUGACUGUUGUGUUGAAUAAGAGAAUAGAAAAAAACACUCCUGAGUGUGUUUUUAUUUCCUCUCAGUUUCCAAGGCUCUGUUGUCUAUCACUUUGUUUUAUAGAUAAAAGUAAGGUAAGUCUGGGAAAUAUUUAUACCUGCCACCCCCUUCCCCGUUGGGAUUUCGGCUACUAAUCUUAAAGACUUAAUCGUUUAUGAGAACCCUUAUCAUUUAGACCAAUAAAUAAUUACUGAACCCAUAAAUUGGAGACCUUUACUUAAAUCUUAUUUCAGUUUUGUGACUUUUUCUUCUUUAGCUGCCCAAUGGGUUCUUCCUGCCUACUGCCCAGAUAGAGCCAAUUUAUCAAGGCAGGGAAUUGCAAUAGAGAAAGAGUUUUUACACACAUAGAUCUUGCGGAACAGAAGACUGGAAUUUUAUUAUUACCCAGAUCAGCCUACCUGAGCAUUUGGGGGCUAUUUUCAAAGGUAGUCUGGGGGAAGGGGUGGGAGUGGCUAGGCAAUGGGUGCUUGCUGCUGAUUGGUUGGGGGCACAAUCAUGGGGGUGUGGGAAAUGGUACUCCUAUGCUCUGAGUGGCUUCUGGGUGAGGCCACAGGAGUGGUCAGUGGGUCCAACCAAAAAACCUGAACAGAUAUCUCAAAAGGCCAAUCUUAGUUUCUCCAGUAGUGAUGUUAUCUGAGGGAGUAAUUGGGCAAGUUGCAUAUCCUGUGACCUCUGGAAUAGUGGCUGGCAAUUGUUUAUGUCUAUACCUUAGCUGAAUUCAGGUUCCUCUGUUGCCUAGCUUCGUGGUCCCUCAUUAGCUUUACAAAGGUGGUUGAAUUUUGGGGAAGAGCUGUUACCAUUUAAACUAUAAACUAAAUUUCUCCCAAAAUUAGCUUGGUUUAAGCCCAGGAAUAAUUAAGGGCAGCUUGAAAGCUAAAGGCAAGAAGAGAAUUGGCUAAAAUCUCCCCACUGCUAUGUUUUCACUGAUAUAAUUUUUGCAAAGGCAGUUUUACUUCUAUCUGAUUUUUAACAUUUGAACUUUGACUUCAGUUUAGUUGUAUUUAACAAGUACCUAAGAAGUGCUGGGCUUGGGUGGCACACAAAAGAUUGUCUCUGCCCUUGUAGUAUUUAAAAUCUUAAAAGACAUUCAUUCGAGUAGUUAAUCAUUUGCAGCCGGGUGACCUUUGCUUCGCCUGUAUUUUUAUUUUUUUAUUUUUAUUUUUUUGAGACUGCGUCUCGCUCUGUCACCCAGGCUGGAGUGCAGUGGCACAGUCUCGGCUCAUGGCAACCUCUACCUCCCAGGUUCAAGUGAUUCUCCUGCCUCAGCCUCCCCAAUAGCUGGGAUUACAAGCACCCGCCACCACACCCAGAUAAUUUUUGUAUUUUUAGUAGAGAUGGUGUUUCAUCAUGUUGGCCUGGUGUCGAACUCCUUACCUCAGGUGAUUUGCGUGUCUUGGCCUCCCAGAGUGCUGGGAUUACAGGCAUGAGCCACCACGCCCGGCCUGCUUCCACUGUGUCUUAACAUUCAUUUGGCAUCUUGUCGUUUCCCUAAAUUUUCCAUGUUAGAAAUCUUAAAACUUACAUAUCCUGUAGUUGGACCUCCGUCUCUUCUCCUAUCUUUGCAGCUCUCUCAAUACCCACACUUUCUAUUAGAGUGCCCCCUCCCCCUCACAGCAACAGUGUGCCAGUCCUUCUGUUCCACCUCACCCUCCCCUCCCUGCUGCAGGGACACCUUUUGGCCUUGCAGAGCGUCUCUAUCCAGUUUGGAAGCCCAUGGUUAAACACCUGGAAUAUGCUUCCCACUGGCACCUUUGCCUCCCUUGGACUUGUCUUUUGUGUUGUACCUGCCAGAUAACGCCCCUGUUCAGAUUAACUCUGCUUCUGUCUCCACAUUGCUUUGGUAUCACCAAUUAAAUGGCUGGUCCUCAAUGCAGGGAAAUGUCCCUCAACCCCCUACCCCCAUACCCUUCAGUCAAUUUGUAAACGUUUGUUUAGCUCCUACUGAGUGCUCUGACACUGAGCCAAGGAUGCUGUGGUAUCCUCAUGGAGUUUACAAUCUAGAGGCGAUUCAAGAUAAUAUUCUGCAUAUAUUGGGUUAAAUAAAAUAUUAAAAAUAAUUCGACCAGGCAUGGUGGCUCACUUUGGGUGGCCAAGGCAGCAGAAUCACUCAAGCUUAGGAUUUUGAGCCUAGCCUGGGCAACAUGGCGAAACCUGUCUCUAUAAAAAAUCAGCUGGGUGUGGUGUCAUAUGCCUGUGACCCCAGCUACUGGGGAGGCUAAGGUGGGAGGAUCACCUGAGCCCAGGAGGUUGAGGCUGCAGUGAGCUGUGAUUGUGCCACUGCACUCCAGCCUGGGCAACAAGAGUGAGACUCUGUCUCAAAAUGAUAAUAAUUCAUUCACUUGUUUCUUUUCGUUUUUUAAACAUAGCUACUGGUACGUUUGAAAUGACACAUGUGGCUCAAGUGAUCUUUCUGUUGGAUGAUGCUGGCAUAGGGUGUUUGGGUUAUGAGAAGGGAAACUGCCCUAGUCUCUGCAAAGUGGGGUAUCACUGAAGACUUCCUGAAGAAGUUGUCCUUAAACAGAUAUCUGGCUGAGUAGGUGUUACACAGGUAAACCCUCAGAGGAGGCAGUCAGAGGUGGAUGGCACUUUGAGGGAGGGGGAGGAGGUGGAUGAGAGAGAGCUGGGACCAUGGCAGGGGCUGAGGCCAGGGAGGUAGGCCAUGGCCUGAUCAUAUGGGUCUUGUUAGCCCCAAUGAGGGUUUUGUUCUUCAUCACUCAUGAUUUAGUCCAAAACUUCAUCAUUACAAACCCUUUUAUCCAACUCCACCUCUUCUAUAUAGUCUGCAGAUAAUCUGGUUAUUUCAUGGAGGAAAUGAGAUGAUCUGCUGUGAUUUCUCUAGGACUUUUCUGUCUCUCCCUUUCCGAACUUUACCUACUUAAGUCUCAGAUCUGUUUUUCCAAAUGUGCCUGUUAUCUCUUCAAGUCUCCUUCAGGAGCGGCUUUAUCAAUUAACUCCCUUCUUUUCUAUGUUUAAUCUCUUUCUCCCUGCUUUCUUUUUCACACCAGCCUAUAAAUAUGCUCCAAUCUUUAACCUUGUAAAACAAACACAGUUCCAUUGACCCCACAUUCUUCUCUAAUUAUUGUUCUUAAAGCAUAACAUUUUUUAAAUUCCAUAUUUUAAAGCAGUGUGUUCAAAAUAUAUGUCAUCAAUAUGAAAUUGUAAAUGUGAUUUGACAUUCUUUUUUCCCAUAUUAAGUACUGAAAUCUAGUGAAAUGGUUUGCACUUAGACAGUAUAUCUCAGUUUGGAUGCUGAAUUUUCAGUGGUUGAAGUAAAAUAAAUUCUACCAAAAUUAUGAAUAUUUAACAGAAUAAUAUUUUACAUUGCUUCAGCUUUUUAUUGUGGCAACCACAUAAAAUUUACUAUCGUAACCAUUUUUAAGUGUACACGUUUAAAUAUAUUCACAUUACAGUGCAACAGAUCUCCAAAACUUUUUCAUCUUAUGAAACUGAAGCUCUGUACCCAUUAAACAACUUCCCAUUUCCUCCUCUCCCCAGUCCCUGGUAACCACUCUUCUACUUUUUAGAAUUUGAGUACUUUAGAUACCGCAUGUAAAUGAAAUCAUACAAUAUAUGUCUUUUUUUGUGUGACUUGCUUAUUUCACUUAGGAUGAUGACCUCAAGGUUCAUCCAUGUUGUAGCAUGUGACAGAAUUUCCUUCCUUUGUAAAGCUGAAUAAUAUACCAUUGUAUACAUAUACCACAUUUUGUUUAUCUGUCGGUAGACAUUUGGGUUCCUUCUACCUCUUGGCUAUUGCUCAUAGUGCUGCCAUAAGCAUGAGUGUACAGAUGUCUCUUUGAGACCCUGCUUUGAAUUCUUUUGGAUGUAUACCCAGAAGUGGGAUUAUUAGAUCAUAUGGUAGUCGAACUUUUUGAGGAACCUCCAUACGGUUUUUCAUUGCGGUUGCACUUGUUUUACAAUCUCACUGUCAGUGCAGAAGGAUUCCAGUUUCUCUACAUGCUCUAUGUUCUCACCAACACUUGUUCUUUUCUGUUUUAAUAGUAGCCAUAUUAAUGGGUAUGAGGUGAUAUCUCGUGGUUUUGAUUUGCAUUUUCCUGGGAUUAGUGAUGCUGAACUUCUUAUAUGCUUGUUGGCCAUUUCUGUAUCAUUUUUGGAGAAAUGUCUGUUCACAUCCUUGGCCUGUUUUUUUUGUUCUUAUUGUUGAGAUGUAGGAGUACCUCACAUAUUCUGGAUAUUAACCUCUUAUCAGAUACGAUUUGCAAAUAUUUUCUCCUUUUCAUUCUGUUGAUGUGUCCUUUGAUGUGCAAAAGUUUUUAAUUUUAAUGUAGUCCCAUUUGUCUAUUUUUGCCUGUGCUUUUAGUGUCAUAUCCAAGAAAUCCUUGCCAAAUCCAGUGUCAUGAAGUGUUUCCAAUAUGUUUUCUUCUAGGAGUUUUAUAGUUUCAAGUUUUACAUUUAGGUUUUUAGUCCAUUUUGAGGCAAUUUUUGAAUAUGGUGUAAGAUAAGGGUCCAAACAAAAUAUUUUGAGCAUAUUGCUGAGACCCUGCUUAUAGCAAAGAGAGGGAAAGGUCUGAAAUACAUGGAAUAGUUUUAAAUUGGGAGAAUUGAUGUCGCUUAUUGGGCUAGAAUACAGUUUUCAGCUGCUUCAUAGUAUAUUUUAGUGUGAAUUUCUCUGUUGUUUUUAUUUCUUAUAGUUGCAAGAUACCAAUUUGGAAACAGUCGAUAGUCUGGGUUUAGCUGAAGCUGAAAUAUAAAAUUGGUAGGGAGAGGCCAGGUAUCACAGUGCAUGUGGUUGUAUCCUGUGCCUCUGCUACUAAAUAUGUCAAGCAUUUGAUCAGUAGUAGCAGUGCAUGACCUUUUAAGACCACUAUGCGAAGGCUAUUUAAUAGAUUUCAAGUGUCCAUAGCAAUUAGUUCCCACAUGAAAUAUUUAUUAAUCUCAUGGAUUUCUCAGUUUUAGGCUUUGUGCUUUUAUUAUAGAUGAGAUGUAUUAAUUGAUACUUCAAUAGACUAAUUUUAGAUUUUGCUAAAAAUAGACAUAAUUCUAUUUUGGGACACUGACCUAUUCUUUUUCCGGUAUAUGUAGUACAUUUAUUAGCACAUUUGAAUUUCUUUUCUGUUUUUAAUGGAGUAUGAUAACAUUAAGAAACCAUUCAGGAUUUAUUUUGAGAGUCUGGAUUUUUUUCAAUGGUAUAGUACCUAUUUUUUGAAAGGAUUAAAAACUUUUAAUGAAUCCCUUUUGCAGAAUGUAGAAGGAUGGUAAAAUCUUGAGUACUGUUAUUAAACAUCAGUCAACUUUCAACUAAUUUAUGUUGUAUUAACUUUUUUCCUAUAAAAUGAUUACCUGUAACACAGUUGCUCUGCAUGAUUUUAGUCUUUCUAAAUGUGAUAGUGACUAUAUUUUCUCUUUCUACAGUUUGGGUUCACCUGAAAGUUGGUGCUGGAGGAAAGCAAACCAUUAUGUAGUUCUUAAGUUGUUUGUUUAUAAUAUAACUUUCUUUGUCUUCAAAAAGAAUCACUCUGGGCCAGGCGCAGUGGCUCACGCCUGUAAACCCAGCACGUUGGGAAGCCAAAGCAGGCAGAUCACCUGAGGUCAGGAGUUCGAGACCAGCCUGGCCAACAUAUAAUGAAACUCUGUCUCUACUAGAAAAUACAAAAAUUAGGUGGGCAUGGUGAUGCACGCCUGUAGUUCCAGCUACUUGGGAAGCUGAGGCAGGAGAACUGCUUGAAUCCGGGAGGCGGAGAUUGCAGUGAGCCAAGAUCGUGCCACUCUACUCCAGCCUGGGCAACAGAGCGAGACUCCAUCUCUUAAAAAAAAAGAAAAAAAAAAUCACUGUUGGUUAUUUGAACCUUUUGAAAAGAAAAUGAUUCUGUUAAUGAAAAACAGGCCAGGCGCAGUGGCUUAUGCCUGUAAUCCCAGAACUUUGGGAGGCUGAGGCAAGUGAAUUACAUGAGGCCAGGAGUUCAAGACAAGCCUGGUCAAAAUGGCAAAACCCCGUCACAAAAAUUAGCUGGGCAUGGUGGUACACAUCUAUAGUCCCAGCUACUCUGGAGGCUGAGGCAAGAGAAUCGCUUGAACCUGGGAGGCAGAGGUUGCAGUGAGCCAAGAUCGUACCACUGCACUCCAGCCUGGAUGACAGAACAAGACUUUGGCCCCCCACCAAAACAAAACAAAACAAAAAACUCAAAGAAAUUGCUCUCUAAGUACACUAGGAUUUAUGGAAGGAUAUCUUUCUGGACAAUAAAGCUUAAUAUUCUUAAAAGUAAUAUUUUAAAUUUAAUUUAAAAUUUAGCAAUAUCUCAAUUUUAAAGAAUGUUUUUCUGUUUGGUUACUCUUGGGGAUUAAGCAGCACAUCUGUUUGAUUUACCUUAUUGUAUACAUUAUAAACUACAUGAAGAUAUAAGGGAUACAUGUUGAUUUUCUUUUUUAAAAUCGCAGUGUAUAUUUUUAAAAUUAAUACAUGCUUAAUGUAGAAAAUGCAGGAAAUCAUAAACUAUGCAAAGAGAAUAAACAUUACUAAUCCCACCAGUUAUAAUUCUUUUAAAAUAAUAUUUUCCAACAAAUAUUUGAAUGCCUAUUCUGUGCUGUGUACCAUUCUAGAUAUUUGGGAUAGAAAAGUGAAUUAUAGAAGUUCUUGUUCUCAGAAAUCUAGUCUAGAUUAUAAUUUCAGUAUGAUUACUCUAUUUUGAUAACAUAUUUAGAUGACAAAAGCAUAGAGUUGUGACAAGGCAAAAUAAAAAUUUAUUAGCAGUUACGAGUAAAGAAUAGUUUCAAGCAAACAUAAAUUUUAGCCUUUUCAUGACUGCAGGUCCUAAGAUAACUGAAUACAUAUAUGUCUUCUUUUCCCACUGGGUGUUUAUUGAAUGCCUGUUAUGUGCCUGGCACUGUUCUACAUGGUGAGACUAUAGCAAUGAGCAAGACAGGUGGGAUCUCUGUUCUCAUGGAGUUUACAUGCUGUGGGGCAGGAAGAGAAACAACAGCAAAUAGUGUAUGUGUUCAGAUGGAUACUUCAUGAAAAACAAGCCUGAGAAAAACACACCUUGACUUUAGUCAGAUACAUCACUGUCUGUUAAAGGAAACCAAGCGUGAAGUGGAAGUCUAACACAUGAGGAUACAGAAUUGAUUCAAAAUGGGAACAACAAGUGAUGAGAUGGUGUCUGUGGAACAGACCUCCUCCUCUUCUCUAAACCCCCUGUGUUUUGAAUGUGGCCAACAGCACUGGACAAGAGAAAACCAUUUGUACAAUUACCAGAAUGAAGUGGAUGAUGACCUAGUCUGCCAUAUUUGCCUUCAACCUCUGCUGCAGCCACUAGACACACCCUGUGGACAUACAUUCUGCUACAAGUGCCUCAGAAACUUUUUACAAGAGAAAGAUUUCUGUCCGUUGGACCGGAAAAGACUUCAUUUUAAGUUGUGCAAGAAGUCUAGUAUUCUAGUUCAUAAACUCCUAGACAAAUUAUUAGUUUUAUGUCCAUUUUCUUCAGUGUGCAAAGAUGUAAUGCAACGUUGUGAUCUGGAGGCACAUCUCAAAAACAGAUGUCCUGGAGCUUCUCAUCGGAGAGUUGCCCUGGAGAGAAGGAAAACUAGUAGAACUCAAGCAGAGAUUGAGAAUGAAAAUGGGCCCACUCUACUAGAUCCUGCAGGUACCUUAUCUCCAGAAGCAGACUGUUUGGGGACAGGCGCAGUGCCUGUGGAGCGGCACUUGACAUCAGCGUCUCUUUCCACAUGGAGUGAGGAGCCUGGCCUUGACAACCCUGCCUUUGAGGAGAGCGCUGGAGCUGACACCACACAACAGCCACUUAGUUUACCAGAAGGAGAAAUCACCACGAUUGAAAUUCAUCGGUCCAAUCCUUACAUUCAGUUAGGAAUCAGCAUUGUGGGUGGCAACGAAACACCUUUGAUUAACAUUGUCAUCCAGGAGGUCUAUCGGGAUGGGGUCAUUGCCAGAGACGGGAGACUUCUUGCUGGAGACCAGAUUCUUCAGGUCAACAACUACAAUAUCAGCAAUGUGUCCCAUAACUAUGCCCGAGCUGUCCUUUCCCAGCCCUGCAACACACUGCAUCUUACUGUGCUUCGAGAGAGGCGCUUUGGCAACCGAGCACACAACCAUUCUGAUAGUAACUCUCCACGAGAAGAGAUUUUCCAAGUGGCUCUUCAUAAACGGGACUCUGGUGAACAGCUUGGCAUUAAAUUGGUGCGAAGGACAGAUGAGCCAGGGGUUUUUAUUCUUGACCUGUUGGAAGGGGGGUUGGCUGCCCAGGACGGCAGGCUAAGCAGCAAUGACCGAGUGCUGGCCAUCAAUGGGCACGACCUGAAGUAUGGAACUCCGGAGCUUGCUGCCCAGAUUAUUCAGGCCAGUGGAGAGAGAGUGAAUUUAACAAUUGCUAGACCAGGGAAACCCCAGCCUGGUAACACCAUUAGAGAAGCAGGAAAUCAUAGCAGCAGCAGCCAGCACCACACACCACCACCGUAUUAUAGCAGACCAAGCUCACAUAAGGAUCUUACUCAGUGUGUUACAUGCCAAGAAAAACACAUUACUGUAAAGAAGGAACCACAUGAAUCCCUUGGCAUGACCGUUGCUGGGGGCAGGGGAAGUAAGAGUGGUGAGCUGCCCAUCUUUGUGACCAGUGUGCCACCCCAUGGCUGCCUUGCACGAGAUGGCAGAAUAAAGAGAGGUGAUGUGUUGCUAAAUAUCAACGGCAUUGAUUUGACCAAUUUAAGUCACAGUGAGGCAGUUGCAAUGCUGAAAGCCAGUGCCGCGUCCCCUGCUGUUGCCCUUAAAGCACUUGAGGUCCAGAUUGUUGAGGAGGCGACUCAGAACGCGGAGGAGCAGCCGAGUACUUUCAGCGAAAAUGAGUAUGAUGCCAGUUGGUCCCCAUCAUGGGUCAUGUGGCUUGGGCUUCCCAGCACACUUCAUAGCUGCCACGAUAUAGUUUUACGAAGAAGUUACUUGGGAAGUUGGGGCUUUAGUAUCGUUGGUGGAUAUGAAGAGAACCACACCAAUCAGCCUUUUUUCAUUAAAACUAUUGUCUUGGGAACUCCUGCUUAUUAUGAUGGAAGAUUAAAGUGUGGUGACAUGAUUGUGGCCGUAAAUGGGCUGUCAACCGUGGGCAUGAGCCACUCUGCACUAGUUCCCAUGUUGAAGGAGCAGAGGAACAAAGUCACUCUGACCGUUAUUUGUUGGCCUGGCAGCCUUGUAUAGAUUUUGGAAAUUGGUUUCAAAUCUUGCAUCUUCCUUUUUUAGAUUUUUGAAAGAAAACCCUUUGGUUUCAUUGUGUUUGUGGUUUAGGAGCUGCUGACACUGCUGGUAUACACAGGGCCAAAACCCACUAAGAUUGUCCGUUUAUGUUUAUUUAAAUGGUUUCCUAAGUUAGUUACAUUUCUUUUAGCUUGGAAACAGUCUUCCACUAACCUUUGUGAGUUUAUAUUUUCAGAAUUCAGACUUAGUUGUUAAAAUGUUACCUAUGGUAAUGAGCAAAGCUCACCCAAACUGUGCCCCAGAUGGAGUAAAGACCUUCUGGUGGGUCUUUGUUUUCAGUAACUGAAUCAUAGAACGAGUUCUGUAUCCCUCAGGCCUGAUGUCAGCAAAGCCAGUAACAACAGCGUGUACUGCCACUGUCAUAACCAAUACCAUGAAUGAAUAUACUUUAAAUUUUGGUGAUAACUGUUCCCCAUUUUUUUUUGAACCACAGUCUCACUCUCACCCAGGCUGGAGUGCAGUGGCACAAUCUCAGCUCACUGCAAGCUCCGCCUCCUGGGUUCACGCCAUUCUCCCACCUCAGCCUCCCGAGUAGCUGGGACUACAGGCGUGUGCCACCAUGCCCAGCUAAUUUUUUGUACUUUUAGUAGAGACGGGGUUUCACCGUGUUAGCCAGGAUGGUCUCGAUCUCCUGACCUUGUGAUCUGCCCGCCUCAGCCUCCCAAAGUGCUGGGAUUACAGGUGUGAGCUGCCGCACCCGGCCGUUCCCAUUUUUUAUUGGUGCCAACAUUUCAAAACUUCAUACUGUUUAUAAACUGAUUUUCUGGUUUAUUUCUACUGUAAUCUCUCAAUAUUCAUAGAAGAUGAAGAAAUAAGUCUGACAACACUAAAGAAAUUUCUUAAUAUACUAUUAUUAGAAUAGUAGAGGAUAAAAGAUAAUGUUAUCCAGUUACAAAGGAAUUUGGAUGAUAAUUAUAACUUAAUGUUAGAGAUGGUAAAGCUGCACUUACUUGAACAGCCCAAAAGCAUUAAAAAUCUAUUUCCAGAGGAAUGUUUUGCUAUGUAGGGAAAUUUUGAAGUAGUUUUUGCUAAAAAAUUAUUUCUAGAGUUGUGUUAUUCUUAGCAGUAAUCUUGGCUAGAAAUGUUUUUGUGAUUUAUGCGAUUAAACGAAAUGAUAAAGAUAAAACCAUAUUAUUAAAUACCUAUAUAUCACAGCUAAGUAGGAGAAAGGGAGACCUUUUUAUUUUGUUCAGGUAGGAGUAUUUCUUGUGUAUUUUAGAAACAAUUAUUUUUCCCAUUAUUUCUUAUGAGAUUAGUUGUUUCAAGUAGGAGACAGAAAAGUUCUGUUUUGUUGGAAAUGUAGGUUUUAGAUGUAUCUUUCAGUCAGCUCUCAGUCACUAGACUAUUUCAUAUUUUUUGAAAUGUUUUUGAAAAUUAUGACUAGCCCAUUUUUUGUCCUUUAUUCAACAUACUUAUCCUCUGAACACAUAAAUAAGUGAAUAAGAUAAAAAUAUCUUUACCUUAUUAAUAUUAUACAUACUUGAAAAAAAUUUCAUUUAGAAACCUAGUUCAGAAUCUGAGCAAAUUUACAAGUGACCUCUGUAAUAAAUGGUAUUGAUAAUCAGAGAAUGUAUUUCAGAAUACUACAGUACAAUAUAUUAUGAAGCAUGACCACUUUAUUUUGAAACUUAGCAAUUGUAUUGCUGGGGUUUAUUGUAUCUGUAGCAUGUCACUGAUUAUUUCAGUUAGUUUUAUAAUGAUUUUUAAAAAACAUAUCUAUUUGGAAUAAGAUACAGCAACAAUCAUUGCUACUGACUUGUUCAACCCCUUAGUUACACUGUAUGAUCAACAUAUAACAAGAUACAGUGGAAUGGCCCAUACAGUAUAUUACUGUUGUGUGAUGAUUGGCUUUGGAAGCAGUUUGAUUUUGAAAUGCUUUGAUAUUCUAAUUGACAUGGAACAAGUUUUUUCCCUGCUCCCCAAAUAGAAUUUUGUAACCAACUUUGCUAUUUUUUUAAAGUUUGUAAGAAUGUGUCAUUUCUUGGGGAGUAGCCAUCCAUCAACAAAUAUCCUGACUGCUACUUUGUUAUAUACAAAAUACUUACAUUGAACCUGGUGGCAUAAUGAGUAUUUUGAAAGAAGAAAUUUCUUCACUCUCAUUUUUAUAGAAAUCUUGGAAUCAGCUUAAGCUGUAGCUUUUAUGACAAAAGACAGUCAUUUUUGGUCAGAGUGAUAUUUGGUGACGGAAACUUGUUCAUAAUUUAUUGUUACUAUAGAACUAUUUGGAUUUUCUCAUUUUUAGUUCUGAUAGUUAAAUAUUUUGGUUUGUUCUGUGCCUUCAGUUUAAAUUAUUUCAGGAUUUUUCAGAUGUUUAAAUAAUGGUGUGAAUCAUUCAGGAUGGAAAUAAAAGUCAUCCUUUCUGUAA